AGUGGCGGGCGCGACACUAUCCGUGCGGCCAGGCGGAGGUGAGUGCGCGGCGGCCGGAUGGGCGGGACGGGCGUGGAGGACGCCGAGCACCGUGGCGCGCGCUCACGUCCGCGUCCCCAAGGGCUGCGCUCCCUCAAGCGCAGUGCCCAGAACUCGGAGCCAGCCCGGCCCGGGGGACCCUGCUGGCCAAGGAGGUCGUCAGUCCGGUCUUGUCUUCCAGACCCGGAGGACCGAAGCUUCCGGACGACGAGGAACCGCCCAACAUGGCCUCGGAGAGUGGGAAGCUUUGGGGUGGCCGGUUUGUGGGUGCAGUGGACCCCAUCAUGGAGAAGUUCAACGCGUCCAUUGCCUACGACCGGCACCUUUGGGAGGUGGAUGUUCAAGGCAGCAAAGCCUACAGCAGGGGCCUGGAGAAGGCAGGGCUCCUCACCAAGGCCGAGAUGGACCAGAUACUCCAUGGCCUAGACAAGGUGGCUGAGGAGUGGGCCCAGGGCACCUUCAAACUGAACUCCAAUGAUGAGGACAUCCACACAGCCAAUGAGCGCCGCCUGAAGGAGCUCAUUGGUGCAACGGCAGGGAAGCUGCACACGGGACGGAGCCGGAAUGACCAGGUGGUCACAGACCUCAGGCUGUGGAUGCGGCAGACCUGCUCCACGCUCUCGGGCCUCCUCUGGGAGCUCAUUAGGACCAUGGUGGAUCGGGCAGAGGCGGAACGUGAUGUUCUCUUCCCGGGGUACACCCAUUUGCAGAGGGCCCAGCCCAUCCGCUGGAGCCACUGGAUUCUGAGCCACGCCGUGGCACUGACCCGAGACUCUGAGCGGCUGCUGGAGGUGCGGAAGCGGAUCAAUGUCCUGCCCCUGGGGAGUGGGGCCAUUGCAGGCAAUCCCCUGGGUGUGGACCGAGAGCUGCUCCGAGCAGAACUCAACUUUGGGGCCAUCACUCUCAACAGCAUGGAUGCCACUAGUGAGCGGGACUUUGUGGCCGAGUUCCUGUUCUGGGCUUCGCUGUGCAUGACCCAUCUCAGCAGGAUGGCCGAGGACCUCAUCCUCUACUGCACCAAGGAAUUCAGCUUCGUGCAGCUCUCAGAUGCCUACAGCACGGGAAGCAGCCUGAUGCCCCAGAAGAAAAACCCCGACAGUUUGGAGCUGAUCCGGAGCAAGGCUGGGCGUGUGUUUGGGCGGUGUGCCGGGCUCCUGAUGACCCUCAAGGGACUUCCCAGCACCUACAACAAAGACUUACAGGAGGACAAGGAAGCUGUGUUUGAAGUGUCAGACACUAUGAGUGCCGUGCUCCAGGUGGCCACUGGCGUCAUCUCUACGCUGCAGAUUCACCAAGAGAACAUGGGACAGGCUCUCAGCCCCGACAUGCUGGCCACUGACCUUGCCUAUUACCUGGUCCGCAAAGGGAUGCCAUUCCGCCAGGCCCACGAGGCCUCCGGGAAAGCUGUGUUCAUGGCCGAGACCAAGGGGGUCGCCCUCAACCAGCUGUCACUGCAGGAGCUGCAGACCAUCAGCCCCCUGUUCUCGGGCGACGUGAUCUGCGUGUGGGACUACGGGCACAGUGUGGAGCAGUAUGGUGCCCUGGGCGGCACUGCGCGCUCCAGCGUCGACUGGCAGAUCCGCCAGGUGCGGGCGCUACUGCAGGCACAGCAGGCCUAGGUCCUCCCACACCUGCCCCCUAAUAAAGUGGGCGCGAGAGGAGGCUGCUGUGUGUUUCCUGCCCCAGCCUGGCUCCCUCGUUGCUGGGCUUUCGGGGCUGGCCAGUGGGGACAGUCAGGGACUGGAGAGGCAGGGCAGGGUGGCCUGUAAUCCCAGCACUUUGGAAGGGCAAGGUGCGAGGAUGCUUGAGGCCAGGAGUUUGACACAGCCUGGGCAACACAGGGAGACCCCCAUCUCUACUCAAUAAUAAAACAAAUAGCCUGGCGUGGUGGCCCAUGCAUAUAGUCCCAGCUACUUGUAAGGCUGAGGUGAGAGGACACUUGUGCCCAGGAGUGGAGGCUGCAGUGAGCUAUGAUCACGCCACUGCAUUCCAGCCUGGAUAACAGAGUGAGAACCUAUCUCUAAAAAUAAAUAAAUAAACGAAAAAUAAAUGGAAGCGGAGAAAACUGGGCAAGGGCAAUGAGAGUCGUAGACGGGAAGGGAAGAGGGGGCUCCCAUCAUAGCCUCUGCUCUGUCCAGGCCCCAUCCCCUUCAGACAGGGUAUCACAGUGACCUCCUAGGCCAGGAGCGAUGGCUCACGCCUGUAAUCCUAGCAUUUUGGGAGGCCUGGGCAACAGGAAGACUCCAACUACCAUAUUAAAAAAAACAUGAAUGAAAGCAAAAA